AGAAGCACCUGUGCUCCCAGGAUAAGGGUGAGCACUCAGGAUGACUGUGGAGAAGGAGGCCCCUGAUGCGCACUUCACUGUGGACAAACAGAACAUCUCCCUCUGGCCCCGAGAGCCUCCUCCCAAGUCCGGUCCAUCUCUGGUCCCGGGGAAAACACCCACAGUCCGUGCUGCAUUAAUCUGCCUGACGCUGGUCCUGGUCGCCUCCGUCCUGCUGCAGGCCGUCCUUUAUCCCCGGUUUAUGGGCACCAUAUCAGAUGUAAAGACCAAUGUCCAGUUGCUGAAAGGUCGUGUGGACAACAUCAGCACCCUGGAUUCUGAAAUUAAAAAGAAUAGUGACGGCAUGGAGGCAGCUGGCGUUCAGAUCCAGAUGGUGAAUGAGAGCCUGGGUUAUGUGCGUUCUCAGUUCCUGAAGUUAAAAACCAGUGUGGAGAAGGCCAACGCACAGAUCCAGAUCUUAACAAGAAGUUGGGAAGAAGUCAGUACCUUAAAUGCCCAAAUCCCAGAGUUAAAAAGUGAUUUGGAGAAAGCCAGUGCUUUAAAUACAAAGAUCCGGGCACUCCAGGGCAGCUUGGAGAAUAUGAGCAAGUUGCUCAAACGACAAAAUGAUAUUCUACAGGUGGUUUCUCAAGGCUGGAAGUACUUCAAGGGGAACUUCUAUUACUUUUCUCUCAUUCCAAAGACCUGGUAUAGUGCCGAGCAGUUCUGUGUGUCCAGGAAUUCACACCUGACCUCGGUGACCUCAGAGAGUGAGCAGGAGUUUCUGUAUAAAACAGCGGGGGGACUCAUCUACUGGAUUGGCCUGACUAAAGCAGGGAUGGAAGGGGACUGGUCCUGGGUGGAUGACACGCCAUUCAACAAGGUCCAAAGUGUGAGGAUCCCAUCCAGAAUACCACGUUACAUUUAGCCAUCAUGUCUCCUUGGGAUCCUCUUGGCUGUGACAUUUUCUCAGUCUUUCCUUGUUUUUGAAGACUUUGACAGUUUUGAGGAGCCCACUGGUCAGGUACUUUGUAGAUUGUCCCUUAAAUGGAAUUUGUCUGGUGUUUUUCUCAUGAUUACAUUGGGGUACUGAGUUUCAGGAGGAAGACCAUGGAGAUAAAGGGCCAUUCUCAUCACAUCCUAUGAAGGGUACAUACCAUCAAUAGAAUUCAUUACUGUUGGCGUUGACCUUGAUCUCCAGGCUGGGGUAGUGUUUGCCAAGUUUAUUGACUCCAGAAUUACUCUUUUCUCCCUUUUCCUGUACUGAACUUUUUGGAAGGAAGUCACUAUAUGCAGUUCACACUGAAAGAGUAGGAAGUUACACUCUACUUUUCUCAGAAUGGGAUAUUUACAUAAAAUAUUUGGACAUUUUCUGCCCUAGAGACUUAUCUAUUUGUUUACUUACUCAGACAUUCAUUUAUGUCAGUAUGGACUCACAGAUAUUUCUCUUACACUUUGGGUUAUAAUCCAAUACUAUUUUAUUUGUUUUUUUGUUUUGUUUUUGCUCAAAUUGCUCUGGCUUUGGCCAUUGGGAGCUCCUUCAUUGGUUCCUGUGUCAUUUUGACAUACUUCCCUCAGUUUUUUUUUUUUUUUUUUUUUUUUGGUAACUAAGCAUCUCCUUACUUUCUGGUACUACAAGAUGCUCCAGGCUCAUCUUGAGUAUUUCCUGCCCCAGUUCUAGAGUCAGCCAUUUCUCUAAUGAGCCCUGGUUUCCUUUUUUUGGAGAAUGGUGUUAGAAAUCAAAACCUGGGGGCUGUGUGGCUGUUGCUAUUUGAACAUCAUUGCCUCUCCCAGCUGAGAGAGCUAAGUAAUAUUUGUGUGUACAUCUAAUUUUUUUUGAAAAGAUCAUUAUGCUUGCACCAUGGUGACAGGACUUGAGAGGGGGUAAGAGGAGAGGCAGGGAGAACAGUUAGGAGACGAACGGAAUAAAAGCCAGGUGGUUUGCAUUCAGGCCUGUAAAUGUGUUGAAUUGUUGUUGCUGUAUUUUGUAGGGUGUAAAAUCAGGACACUUUGUACUGCUGAAUACAAGUGCUCACAUCAUGUCAAGAAGCUGUCCCUACUAUUAAAUAAAAUGUCCUGGAUUAAAAAACAUAAA